CCAUGCUGUCCGGAUGGUGCCUGUGAUUACAGAGGAAAUACCUUUCAACUGGAAGAUAUCAUUAAACACAGGAAAAGAGAUCAGUACAUCGAGAAAUUAACAAAGGAGAGGGACGCUCUGAGUCUGGAACUGUACAGGAACACCAUAACCGAUGAGGAGUUGAAGGAGAAAAAUGCCGAACUACAAGAAAAACUUCGACUUGUAGAAUCUGAAAAGUCUGAGAUCCAGCUCAACGUAAAGGACCUUAAAAGGAAGCUGGAAAGGGCCCAGCUCCUGCUGCCACAGCAGCAGCUGCAGGUGGAGGCUGACCGCCUGGGUAAGGAGCUACAGAGUGUGUCAGCAAAGCUCCAAGCCCAGGUGGAAGAGAACGAGUUGUGGAACCUCCUGAACCAGCAACAAGAGGAGAAGAUGUGGAGGCAGGAGGAGAAGAUACAGGAGCAGGAAGAGAAGAUGUGUGAGCAGGAGCUGAAGAUAAGGGAGCAGGAGGAGAAGAUGUGGAGGCAGGAGGAGAAGAUGCAUGAGCAGGAAGAGAAGAUACGGGAGCAGGAGGACAAGAUGUGGAGGCAGGAGGAGAAGAUACGGGAGCAGGAAGAGAAGAUACGGGAGCAGGAGGAGAAGAUGUGGAGGCAGGAGGAGAAGAUACGGGAGCAGGAUGAGAAGAUACAGGAGCAGGAGGAGGAGAUGUGGAGGCAGGAGGAGAAGAUACGGGAGCAGGAGGAGAAGAGGCAGGAGAAGAUGUGGAGGCAGGAGAAGAAGAUGCGCGAGCAGGAUGAGAAGAUACGGGAGCAGGAGGAGGAGAUGUGGAGGCAGGAGGAGAAGAUACGGGAGCUGGAGGAGAUGAUGCAAGAUCAGGAGGAGAAGCUGCGGGAGGUGGAGGAGAAAAUGCAGGAGGAGGAGGAAAAGAUGCAGGAGCAGGAGGAGAAGAUACAGAGGCAGGAGGAGAAGAUCCAGGAGCAGGAGGAGAAGACGUGGAGGCAGGAGAAGCUGCUCAAGCAGGAAGAGAAGAUAUGGGAGCAGGAGGAGAAGAUGUGGAGGCAGGAGGAGAAGAUGUGGGAACAGGAGGAGAAGAUGCAGGAACAGGAGGAGAAGAUGCAGAGGCAGGAGGAGAAGAUGCGGGAGCAGGAAGUGAGGCUGUGGCAGCAGGAGGAGAAGAUGCAGGAACAGGAGGUGGAGCUGAAGAGCCAAGAGGCUCAGAGUCUGCAGCAGCAGCAAGACCACUACCGGGGUCACCUGCAGCAGUACGUGGCCGCCUAUCAGCAGCUGGCCUCUGGGAAGGAGGCACUGCCCAGCUGCAGCAGCAGGAAGCUCAGGGCGAAGCGGUGGCUGAGAUGGCCCACCAAUAGUUGCAGGAGACCCAGCUGAGGGAGUUGAUGAGGGUGGGGCCCUGAGGGGGACGACCUGGCAAACUCGGUGCCUUCUCACUCUCUUUCCU